AUAGAAUGUAAGCUCCAUGAAACCGAGGUUUUGUCUGCUUUGUUCACUGAUGUGUUUCAAGCAAUUAAGAGAGUGUCUGUCAUAUUAAGGGCACUCAAUGAAUAUCUGUUGAGGGAGCAAACUUGCUGAAUCAUACUGUUAAGGAAAUCAAAAGAAAACCUUGAAGGAGGCAUUUCUCAUCUGACGUUCACAAACAUCUUGUGAUUUAGGCAGGCCAAGUGUUAUCCUCAUAUUUUUGAAAGAUUAAAUUUCAUCACAAACCUAGAGAUUUUAAGUUGUGCUAGCGUGUGAAAUUUAUUUUGCAGAAUAUUUUACUUGAAAGGUAUGUGUCUUUUUACCCUGAGUCAUUUUCCUGCCAUUUUCUUUAUCUACAGGGAAUUUCAUAAUAUUCAUUUGCUUCUCUUAUUUUGACAAGUAAAAUGAGCAGUCUCCUAUGUCUCAAACCUGCCUUUCAAAUAUUGCUAUGAAAGAACAUUGGAGCUAUCAUGUCUGGAAGUGUGUUUGCAAUCUAAUUUUACCUAUUCACUCUCCUCCUUAAAUUUUUCUUUUGUGACUUUUCUGCAACCAGUAAGGGAAACUCAGAUUAUCAUGAGAAUCUUUCUAAAUCCCUCCAAUUUUCGUAACUUCACCAGGACUUGCCAAGACAUCACAGGUGAAUUUAAAAUGUGCUCCUCGUGUUUGGUUUGUGAGUCUAAAGGAAACAUGGAUUUUAUUUCUCAGGAACAAACAUCAAAAGUUCUUAUCAGGAGAGGAUCAAUGGAAGUGAAAGCAAAUGAUUUUCAUUCACCUUGUCAGCACUUUAACUUCAGUGUAGCUCCUCUGGUUGACCACUUGGAGGAAUAUAACACUACCUGUCAUCUAAAAAACCACACUGGAAGAUCAACAAUCAUGGAGGAUGAGCCAAGCAAGGAGAAAUCGAUAAACUACACUUGUAGAAUCAUGGAAUACCCGAAUGAUUGUAUACACAUUUCUUUGCACCUAGAGAUGGAUAUAAAAAAUAUCACUUGUUCCAUGAAGAUCACUUGGUAUAUUUUAGUUCUAUUAGUUUUUAUAUUUUUGAUCAUCCUCACUAUCCGCAAAAUACUUGAAGGCCAGAGAAGAGUGCAAAAGUGGCAGAGUCAUAGAGACAAACCUACAUCUGUUCUCUUAAGAGGAAGUGAUUCGGAGAAACUGAGAGCAUUGAAUGUGCAGGUUCUUUCAGCAGAGACCACGCAGAGGCUGCCUUUGGAUCAAGUCCAGGAAGUGCUUCCCCCAAUUCCAGAACUAUAAGUUACUUCCACAGUGCAUCAGUGAGAUCAAUAUACACGAAUAUCCCCGGGCAAGUUGGACCGAGCCCUUUGAAGAAUACUCAGAAGUUUAUUUUGUGAAUGAGUAGACUGGAAAAUGUUUGUGUCCAGCUGAGGAUGCACAGUUGGAAAGCAGGAGGAAUGCUGACUGGUUGAUGAAAACUAGCUUAAGAGCAUUCAUUCGCUCCAUGAGAUCAAGGGAACAAGAGUGUUUGCAAGAAGCCAUUAUGAGUCAUGGAAAAAAAGAUGAUGAAACCCAUGGAAACAGCAAGAGAAUUCCCACUCUCUCUCUUCUUAAAAAAAAUCUAUCAUUAUACAGCACAGAGUGGAGCCAAGUUUUUAAUUUUGAGGAACCAAAAACAGGAUCAAAUAUGAAAACCCUUUCUUUUAUUGGGCCACAUUGUAGAUGCUGAUUUGAUAAUUGUUUCCUAUGCAGAUAGAUUAUUUUUAUUUCACAGAUUAUUUAAAAGGGAAGAGGGCCUGGUUGUUUAUUUAUAUGUUUGUUUGCAUUUAUGAAUCUUGCUGCCUUUUAGCACCAGGAUGUUUUUAAAAAAAUUCAAAGAGGCCAGGCGCAGUGGCUCAUGCCUGUAAUCCCAGCACUUUGGGAUUCUGAGGUGGGAGGAUCAUGAGGUCAAGGGAUCGAGACCAUCCUGGCCAACAUGGUGAAACCCUGUCUCUACUAAAAACACAAAAAUUAGCUGGGUGUGGUGGUGCGCGCCUGUAGUCCCAGCUCCUCAGGAGGCUGAGGCAGGAGAAUCACUUGAACCUGGCAGGCAGAGUUUGCAGUGAACCAAGAUCACGCCACUGCAUUACAGCCUGGUGCAGAGCAAGACUCUGUCUCAAAAAAAAAAAAAAAAAAAAAUCAAAGAUACCAAUAAAACGAAUUUAAAUAAAAUACUUAAGUACUUUAAUAGCAAAA